GGCUGCAAUGAGAUCAUACCACUGCAUUUCAGCCUGAGCGACAGAGCAAGAACCCUGUCUCUCCAAAAAACCAGCAACCCCCCGCCCCAUGAUGACCAUAGGUCCCAAGUCUCAGAAUUAUAUUUCAUGUAUUUAAAAUUGGAUAUGUAACCGUCUUAGUCCAUACUGUUUUGCCGUAACAAAAUAUCACAGACUGAGUAAUUUAUAAAGAAAUGUAUUUCUCGUAGUUCUUCAGACUGGGAAAUUCAGUAUCAGAGUGCCAGCAUCUGGUGAGGGCUGUUGUGUGGCACCUUGUCAUCCCAUGGCGGGAGGCAGGAGGACAAGAGAAGGUGAGAGAAGUGGGCAAGAUGGCAAAACUCACUUUCAUAAGGAAAUCACUUUCUUGAUAACUACCCCACUCCCCAGAUGGCAUUAAUCCAUUCAGAGCCCUCCUGACCCAAUCACCUCUUGUUAGUGAUUAUACAGAAAAUUUUAUGUACAAUUUCAGUGUGUGUGUGUGUCUGUGAGUGUGGUAGGUUCCUGUGAUUGAAUCAAUUCAAUCAGCUCAGCAUCUUAUGGACCUGUGAUAGUGGGAAGCUACACAAGCAGAAAGGCAGCUGUGGCAUCUGAAGGCAUACCAUGUGCCAGGCUCUGUGUUAUGUGCUGACCUCACCUCCCUACACUGUUGCAUUGGGGAUUAGUUUUCUAGUAUUUGAAUUUUGGGGGACACACUGAGACCAGCAGUACUUUUCAUGGUCCUCACGUUUACCUGCCAUUCAACACACACCACCCUUCUAAUACUAGGAGUUGAGAAUUAGAAGGGGAAGAAUUAGUUUCGACGGGGUCAUUUCUCCCAGGGCUGAUAAAGUAUUCUUGGCCCGCGACAGCGCGUCAUCACUGUCUCUCCCCAAGCAGGGGGGAUGAUUACUGCCAGUUUUUAUCUUGGGACCUCUUUCCCAUGAUGGACAGCAUACAGCGCAUCCUCUUUUGAUGAUAACAUUGUUUUUUUUUUUUUUUUCCAGUAAGAAUCCAGUUCUCUUUUCUUCAUUAUAAUCCUACCCAGGCUGUUCCUAAUUGUCCUACCUUUCCAGAUUUCUUCUUGAUUGGAUUUCAAGCAUAUCUGGAAAUCUUCAUUCACACGUUCACCUUAGCAUUUCUUCCUUGGCGGUGACCUGCAUGUUGCUGGAGUCCUGUGCUGUUGCCCUCUUCUCUUGCAUGCCUGCUGGCAUUUCAGCUGGCCUUUCAGCUAUUGCUGUCCUCAUAGCAGCAUGCCUCUGCCGUGGCGUCCAUCACAUUGCAUGGAAAAGGUUACUGGUUUUUUGCCUGUCCUCCCUCCUAGAUCUUUGCUAUUUGAGGGCAGGGUCCUCUUUUUCUUCUUUGUGUCCCCAGCACAUAACAGAGCCUGGCACAUAGUAUGCCUUCAGAUGCCACAGCUGCCUUUCUGCUCGUGUGGCUUCCCACUAUCACAGGUCCUAAGAUGCUGAGCUGAUUGAAUUGAUUCAAUCACAGGAACCUACCACACUCAAAGACACACACACUGAAAUUAUAUAUAAAAUUUUCUGUGGGCCAGGCAUGGUGGCUCACGCAUGUAAUCCCAACACUUUGGGAGGCUGAGGCAGGCAGAUCAUUUGAGGUCAGGAGUUUGAAACCAGCCUGACCAACAUGGUGAAACCCCAUCUCUACUAAAAAUAAAAAAAAUAGCUGGGCAUGGUGGUGCACGACUGUAGUCCCAGCUACUCGGGUGGCUGAAGCUGGAGAAUUGCUUGAACUUAAGAGGUGGAGGUUGCAGAGACUCCGUCUCAAAAAAAAAAAAAAAAGAAAAAAAAAUUCUGUCUAUGCACAUUUUCAUUAUUCUUACACAGGAGACCAGGACACAAUCAUGUAAGAGCAACCAGACCUAGAACAUCGAAAGAUGAAGUCCCACGUUAAACUUCUAGGACCUUAUCUCUGGCAUCACUCACCAUCCCCCUACCUUUUAUCUCCCCUAUUUCUGUUUAUCCGUUAAAGAUACUAUAAUCUUUUCUUUUCCUGGACAGGAUUAAAACUUAACUAAAAUUUUCCUUGUCCGUUUUUCUCCACCUGCAGUUAGUUGCAAAACCCUUACUGACUGUGUGUCUGAAACUGUUCUUUCAUAAUUUCUUUCCAUUUCCACUGUCAUUUCUAGCACUGGCCCCGUCACCUCUUCCCAGACUAGACCAGGGUUCUUCUCACCCUCCAGUCUCUCUCCCUAACUAACAGUGUGUUCUGCAGACCACAUCCAAAUUAACCUUCCAAGUUUGAUUAUUCUUUCUUUUCUUUGUUCAAAAGUCUUUGGUGACUCCCCAGUACUUAACACAAUUUCCAACUAAUUCAGCAGUGAUCUCCUAGUAGCAAGAGAAUGAUGACUCCAAACCUCAGAGGCCUGGAGCUGUAUUCCAAAGCAGCUCUGAACAUAAAUUCUCUAAUGACAUCUCCCAUUUUAUCUGUAAGAGUCAUGCAAGUAUUUAAGGUAAAAAUAUCAUCCCAAACAACAAGCAACAGCAAUACAAAGUCAAAGUAAAACUCUAGGAACCUGUGCCAUUUUUACCCUGUGGCUUUUUAUAUUCCAGCCACACACCGUGGAACCCAGGGAACACUCACAUCCUAAUUGGAAAAUUGGGUCUAAGCGAUGAAGUCCAGAUGAUUCCAUCUGGUAUCUGAGGCUGUCUGUGGUCAGCUGCGAACCUGCUUUUCCAGAUUUUGUCUCUGGCCAUGCUUGUCCAGUAUACUAGUCACCUAGUAUAAUUGUUCUAGUCACCUAGGAAAUUGUGUUAGGUACUGGAAGACACCAAAGACUUUUGAACAAAGAAAGGAUAAUCAAAAUGGAUUAAACAAACCUAGAGCAUGUUGCAUAGUUUCCAACUUUCGCAGUGCUCAGGAAUUGUUAAUAUGAGUGUGGGGUUUUUUAUUGUUGUUGUUGUUUGUUUGUUUGUUUGAUUGUUUCUGAGACACUCUGGCUCUGUCGCCCAGGUUAGAAUGCAGUGGGUGUGAUCUCGGCUCACUGCAACCUCUGCCUCCCGGGUUCAGGCGAUUCUCCUGCCUCAGCCUCCCCGGUAGUUGGGAUUACAGGCACCCGCCACCACUCCUGGCUAAUAUUUGCAUUUUAGUAGAGACAGGGUUUCACCAUGUUGGCCAGGUGGGUCUCGAACUCCUGACCUCAGGUGAUCCACCUGCCUCAGCCUCCCAAAGUGCUGGGAUUACAGGUGUGAGCCACCACGCCUGGCCAUAUGGACAUUUUUUAUGGGAGAAGACUCAUGGAACUUCUUCUUAGCCUUUUUUAACUUCUGGAGACAGUUUUAGUAAUUCACACAUUUUCAGAAAACCCUAUUCUAGAUUUACACAUAUAUUGGUAUAAUUAGUAUUUUCCAGUUAACCUAAUAUUUAGAGUUGUAGUCAUAUUUGAGGGGAGGAGCUAUUUUGGUUUCCUUUCUGUGUUACUCAGCAUCGAGCCAGUGACACAGCUGUUUGAUGCAAGGCUGAGAGGAAUGACAUGGUUCCAGCAAAGCAGCAACACGGACCUGGCCAGCCUUUGGGGACUCCUGGGAUCCAUCUCUUGGCCAACUGAAAGUGUUAUGUAGCUGGUUUCAGGUCCCUCACCAUUAUACCCACUUGAGCUGAUUUAUACUUUACAGUGUAAAUUGGCAUGGGGCAUGCCUUUGGGAUUAAAUUAAUUUAUACCAAGUUAGAAAGCAUCAGCUGUCAAAGUCAGGGGAGCCUUCUGGAGGCCAGUGUGCUUUUUUUCUUUCUGUAUUCUGAGCCCACACUCCAGGCAUUCUCUCUUGGAUAGCAGCUGGGACAGUCCUUCAAGAGGCCUGCUUUGCAUCUCCUUUGUGUCCUUGCGGUUCCGGGUCCUAUACAGAAGAUCUCUGUCCUUUGACAGAGAUACUACGUAGUAGUUGGUCCCCGUGCAAAUUAGGAAGAUUUGUAACCCUCUUACAUAAAAUACAACAAACACGAUUUUUUUUUCUUUAAACAUUUUCCCCCUCCUUAAAUACACUCAAAGGAAUUACAGUGACCGAAUGGCAGUAGUACAGAUCUGUGAUCUCGAUCCUUAAUCAGAAGUUGAAGAAAAGAGUUUCUCUUUACUACCUCUUUAGCAAAAGAUUAAUGAAAAUUUAUACAGGGAUUAGAAACACAUCAAACAAGAAAAGGUACCUGUAAUGUUAUUUAAGAAAAGUUGUGUUAAAUGGGUUGGUAGGGUUACAAUAAAGGCAUUUAGCAAUAUCCUGCAUAUGUCACUUGACUGUCUCCAGUCUGGAAAUUAUCUUCGUGUAUUAGGCAGGCAGGACUUGCCGAAGUGCAGAAUGGUAAACUGCUUUUCUUAAGAGGUAUGUAAAGGCCCUGUUUCUUCUGCUUGUUCCCGCUGCUGUGAGAGGUUGGGGCUAGUCCCCUUGCUCACUUCUGAGUUGUUUUCCCAGCAGCCACUGCACGGCUCGAAGGAUUUGUCGUUGAGGGUGGAGAAGGUGGAAGGAUGUUGAACAGACUUUUCCCUAAUGAGCUGUGAUGCCAGCUGCAAAGGCGGCAAAUCCUGUUACUCCCUUCAGCUACUCUCUGAAGCUGCAGAGGGGCAGUGGUAACUGGUCUCCCUGCCCUAUGCUGAUUAGCUGCCUUUUCUGCUGUUUUUCCCCCCUUCCUCUUCUGUCCCAGAGCAUCUUGGCAAAGUUCAGAUUUCUGUGCUCACAGCUCAAUGCUCACAGUGAAAAGGAAAUACAAAAGAGGAGGAGAGAAAGUGAGAAGAAAAGAGAGAAAAGGUUGGGGUGGAGGUUUUUAGUAGAGUCCCUUAUUGCCUUAGUCUAAGACUUAAGCUCUGGGUUGAAACCUUAAGUGGUAAAGCUUUGUAAGUAGUAACCUGGAUUUCCAAAUAGUUCUUGCAGAUAGUUUUAUUGGCACAUGAACACAGCAGGCCAUAUAUUAAAAGCAUUUGAAUUUCUAUCGUUUAGAAACCUCCGAAUUUUGAAAAGGACACUUCGCAGUUUUUCCACAAACUAUCAUUGUGAGGAAGAUGAAAUAAUUGUAAGAUAAAUGUUUUCAUGUGGCAUUUACUGUGUGCCACUGCUUCAUUUAAUCAUUACAACCCUUGAAAAUAGACACUUUUAAUGUGAAAAAUAAUUUAUUGUAGUAAACACAUUUUAAAGUGGUCAGUUCAGUAAUAUUAAGUAGAUUCACAUUGUUGUCAAAGAGAUAUCCAAAACUGUUUCGUCUUCCAAAUGCCAGCCGCAUAUCUGAAACACCAUACCCAUUAAAAUAAUGGGGAAACAUUUUAACUGAUCAGCCAGCAUUUUAACUGUUUGGCCAUUUCUUUUGUUCUGCAGGAUUAAAAAUAGCUCUCCUGUUUCUUUCCUUGGCUGUUUUGAUAGAACAUUCUUCCUCUGUAUUUCAUCACAGGAUGGUGAGACCAGGGCUUGUAUUUACUGUGCCUUGGUUUAUCCAUUUGGUACUAACUGGGGGGGGUUUAUAGUUACUAAAGGGAAAGAGAAAAGGCUUUACUCUCCAGGGGUUCGUCACCUAUUCUUGGUUCUCAUCUUUACUGAUUCUGCAUUUUAAGUUCUGCUGAGCUCCAGGGGUAAGUUCAGCAAUGUCUUCAUCACCUCACAAGUUAGCUUGGACCUGCAAAUUUUUGGGUGGGUUUUCUGGGUGGCUUCUGACACAGUAAACAUAAUAUCAUAGAAUUAUAUUUAAAAAGCAAUUUUACAUGUUGAACCCUGUUUUUAAUGACUUCAUGAGUUAGUUACUAUAUUCCAGGGAUGGUGAAAUGGGGAAUAUGGUAGGUAAGGGAGAAGAGUUGGAAUAUUUAAUAAGUGACGCAGAGUUCCUCUCCCUAUGUGUGUCCUUUGAGGGACCAUUUAAGCCUAUUCGAUUCUCCUUGGAAGAGCUAGUCCAGCAUCCCUGAUAUUCUACUUUCUAUUGUGUUAGAAGAAAAGGCACUCCUGACAUUAUUGCUACAAUGUAGAAAACUUGUCUUGCCUCCUUGGAGGAUAGUAUUCUAGCUAGAACCUAGGCAGCGCUGGUGAAAAUGGCCAUGAUAAAGGCGGAAGCCAGAAGAGGAUGUCUGUGUGCCGAAGGCGGAGAUGGAGAAAAAGGAGUUAGAAGCCGCUCUUCACAGAGAUGACGUGGAGUUUAUCAGUGACCUGAUUGCCUGCCUGCUUCAGGGCUGCUAUCAACGAAGAGAUAUCACGCCUCAGACAUUCCACAGCUACCUAGAGGACAUCAUCAACUACCGCUGGGAGCUCGAAGAAGGGAAGCCCAACCCUCUGAGGGAAGCCAGUUUCCAGGACCUGCCUCUUCGCACACGGGUGGAGAUCCUGCACCGACUCUGUGAUUACCGGCUGGAUGCAGACGAUGUCUUCGAUCUUCUAAAGGGCCUGGAUGCAGACAGUCUCCGUGUGGAGCCAUUGGGUGAAGACAAUUCUGGGGCACUAUAUUGGUAUUUCUAUGGAACACGAAUGUACAAAGAGGACCCGGUGCAAGGAAAAUCCAAUGGAGAACUCUCUUUGAGCAGGGAAAGUGAAGGACAAAAAAAUGUCUCAAGUAUUCCUGGAAAAACGGGAAAAAGAAGAGGAAGACCCCCAAAACGGAAGAAACUGCAGGAGGAGAUUCUGUUGAGUGAAAAGCAGGAAGAAAAUUCCUUGGCAUCCGAGCCACAGACAAGACAUGGGUCCCAAGGGCCAGGCCAAGGUACUUGGUGGCUCCUGUGCCAGACAGAAGAGGAAUGGAGACAGGUCACCGAGAGUUUUCGCGAGAGGACCUCCCUUCGAGAACGGCAGCUCUACAAGCUCCUCAGUGAGGACUUCCUGCCUGAGAUCUGCAACAUGAUCGCCCAGAAGGGAAAACGUCCACAGCGCACAAAGGCAGAGUUGCAUCCUAGGUGGAUGUCUGACCACCUGUCCAUCAAACCCGUCAAGCAAGAGGAGACUCCUGUGCUGACCAGAAUAGAAAAACAAAAGCGCAAAGAGGAGGAAGAAGAGCGUCAGAUUCUUCUAGCAGUGCAGAAGAAGGAGCAGGAGCAGAUGCUAAAGGAAGAGAGGAAACGCGAGUUGGAGGAGAAGGUCAAGGCAGUGGAAGAUCGAGCGAAGAGGAGAAAGCUCAGGGAAGAAAGGGCAUGGCUGCUGGCUCAAGGAAAGGAGCUCCCUCCAGAACUUUCCCAUCUGGACCCCAAUUCCCCCAUGAGAGAGGAAAAAAAGACUAAAGACCUCUUUGAGUUGGAUGAUGAUUUCACUGCUAUGUAUAAAGUUCUAGACGUGGUAAAGGCUCACAAGGAUUCCUGGCCCUUCUUGGAACCUGUGGAUGAAUCUUAUGCCCCUAACUAUUAUCAGAUUAUUAAGGCCCCCAUGGAUAUUUCCAGCAUGGAGAAGAAACUGAAUGGAGGUUUAUACUGUACCAAGGAGGAAUUUGUAAAUGACAUGAAGACCAUGUUCAGGAAUUGUCGAAAGUAUAAUGGGGAAAGUAGUGAGUAUACCAAGAUGUCUGAUAAUUUAGAGAGGUGUUUCCAUCGGGCAAUGAUGAAACAUUUUCCUGGAGAAGAUGGAGACACAGAUGAAGAAUUUUGGAUUCGAGAGGAUGAAAAGCGGGAGAAAAGACGGAGUCGGGCUGGGCGAAGUGGUGGGAGCCAUGUUUGGACCCGCUCCAGGGACCCAGAAGGGUCCAGCAGGAAACAGCAGCCCAUGGAGAAUGGAGGAAAGUCGUUGCCCCCCACACGCCGAGCGCCCUCUUCUGGGGACGAUCAGAGCAGCAGCUCCACACAGCCCCCGCGGGAGGUGGGCACUUCCAAUGGCCGAGGUUUUUCUCAUCCCCUGCAUUGUGGUGGGACACCCAGCCAGGCACCCUUUUUAAACCAGAUGAGGCCAGCAGUACCAGGAACAUUUGGCCCUCUGCGAGGAUCAGAUCCUGCCACCUUGUAUGGCUCCUCUGGAGUCCCGGAGCCACACCCCGGGGAGCCUGUGCAGCAGCGUCAGCCUUUCACCAUGCAGCCUCCAGUUGGAAUUAACAGCCUCCGAGGACCCAGGCUAGGCACACCAGAGGAGAAGCAAAUGUGCGGGGGGCUGACACACCUUUCUAACAUGGGCCCACACCCUGGAUCCUUGCAGCUUGGGCAGAUAAGUGGCCCAAGUCAGGAUGGAAGCAUGUAUGCUCCAGCUCAGUUCCAGCCAGGAUUCAUUCCUCCCCGGCAUGGGGGGGCUCCAGCCCGGCCACCAGACUUUCCUGAAAGCUCAGAAAUUCCUCCCAGCCAUAUGUAUCGAUCGUACAAGUACCUGAAUCGAGUACACUCUGCCGUCUGGAAUGGGAACCAUGGUGCUACGAACCAAGGACCCUUGGGCCCAGAUGAGAAGCCCCACCUGGGGCCAGGACCCUCUCACCAGCCUCGCACUCUCGGUCACGUGAUGGAUUCCCGAGUCAUGAGACCACCUGUCCCCCCCAACCAGUGGACUGAACAAUCAGGCUUCCUACCUCAUGGAGUUCCUUCCUCAGGGUACAUGCGACCGCCCUGCAAGUCUGCCGGACAUCGGUUACAGCCACCUCCAGUGCCAGCACCCAGUUCUUUGUUUGGAGCACCUGCCCAGGCUCUUCGGGGGGUGCAGGGAGGGGACUCCAUGAUGGACAGCCCAGAGAUGAUUGCGAUGCAGCAGCUCUCCUCCCGCGUCUGCCCCCCAGGUGUGCCUUACCACCCCCACCAGCCUGCACACCCCCGUUUACCUGGCCCUUUUCCGCAGGUAGCUCACCCAAUGUCAGUCACUGUGUCAGCCCCCAAGCCUGCCCUGGGCAACCCUGGGAGGGCACCGGAGAACAGUGAAGCACAAGAGCCUGAGAAUGACCAAGCAGAGCCGUUGCCUGGCCUUGAAGAGAAACCACCAGGUGUUGGUACUUCAGAGGGGGUCUACCUCACACAACUACCUCACCCCACACCUCCCCUGCAGACUGACUGCACCAGGCAGAGCUCACCACAAGAAAGGGAAACAGUGGGCCCGGAGCUCAAAAGCAGCUCCUCCGAAUCUGCGGACAACUGUAAAGCAAUGAAGGGCAAGAAUCCCUGGCCCUCGGAUAGCAGCUACCCCGGCCCAGCCGCCCAAGGGUGCGUGAGAGACCUCUCCACGGUGGCAGACAGGGGCGCUCUAUCCGAGAACGGAGUCAUUGGGGAAGCAUCUCCUUGUGGAUCGGAGGGGAAGGGCCUUGGUAGCAGUGGUUCCGAAAAGCUGCUCUGCCCCAGAGGCAGAACGUUGCAGGAAACCAUGCCAUGCACGGGACAGAACGCAGCGACACCGCCCAGCACAGACCCCGGUUUGACGGGAGGCACUGUGAGCCAGUUUCCCCCGCUGUAUAUGCCUGGCCUAGAGUACCCGAAUUCAGCUGCCCAUUACCACAUCAGUCCAGGCCUGCAGGGUGUGGGCCCUGUGAUGGGAGGGAAGUCCCCAGCAUCCCAUCCCCAGCAUUUUCCCCCAAGGGGCUUUCAGUCUAACCACCCACAUUCUGGAGGCUUUCCCCGGUAUCGCCCCCCACAAGGAAUGAGGUAUUCCUACCACCCACCGCCACAGCCUUCCUACCACCACUAUCAGCGAACUCCUUACUAUGCCUGUCCACAGAGCUUUUCUGACUGGCAGAGACCUCUCCAUCCCCAGGGAAGCCCAAGCGGACCCCCAGCCAGUCAGCCUCCCCCACCAAGGUCCCUCUUCUCAGAUAAGAAUGCCAUGGCCAGUCUGCAAGGCUGUGAGACACUGAAUGCUGCCUUAACUUCUCCAACCCGUAUGGAUGCAGUGGCUGCUAAAGUCCCAAAUGACGGGCAGAAUCCUGGUCCAGAGGAAGAGAAGCUGGAUGAAUCUAUGGAGAGGCCAGAGAGUCCCAAAGAAUUUUUAGACCUGGACAACCAUAACGCAGCUACCAAGCGGCAGAGCUCGUUGUCAGCCAGCGAGUAUCUCUAUGGAACUCCUCCGCCUCUGAGUUCAGGAAUGGGAUUUGGUUCAUCUGCAUUUCCACCCCACAGUGUGAUGCUGCAGACGGGGCCUCCCUAUACCCCUCAGCGGCCGGCCAGUCACUUUCAGCCCAGGGCUUACUCUUCCCCUGUGGCUGCCCUCCCACCUCACCACCCAGGGGCCACCCAGCCCAACGGCCUCUCUCAGGAGGGUCCCAUCUAUCGCUGCCAGGAAGAAGGCCUGGGUCACUUUCAAGCUGUGAUGAUGGAACAAAUUGGCACUAGAAGUGGAAUAAGAGGACCUUUCCAGGAAAUGUACAGACCAUCAGGAAUGCAGAUGCACCCGGUCCAGUCGCAGGCCUCGUUCCCAAAGACCCCCACAGCAGCAACAUCACAGGAGGAGGUGCCGCCUCAUAAGCCUCCAACACUUCCCCUGGAUCAGAGCUAGUCCAAGGAGGAAAUGAGCCCCAAGCAAUGGAAAGCUGCACACGAAGACUGGAAUGUGGAGAACUGGGGAGUGCCCUGUCAGCUCUAUUCCCAUCACCUGCUCCACCCCUUCACGGCGACCCACUCGUGCCAUACUUGAGCUGGAGCCAGUCACGGGCCCUAAAAGGACACUCCUUAGAUGACUGACACACAGAUUGCAAAGGUCCUCGGCCAGGGAUCUCUUGCACAGCUGAUGUAGACAGUCAGGCAAAACUAAUGAACGUGGAGUUAAUGAUGACUUUUCCAAAUCCUGAGACACUUUUCAGGGAAAAUCACUUUAAACUUGGGGGAGGGGGUAUACUCAAGAAUGGAGUGGUGCUUUUAAACUUUGAUGAGCAGCUAAACUCAGGUAUAUAUUUGGGGAAGGGACUACUCUUAGUAUUAAUGGUUUUGGAGCUGGGUCCAGUUUACAGAAUUUUCAUGUUGCCUUUUAAAAUAAUUUUUGUUGGUGGUGAAUGUAUUGUACAUAAAGUGGGAAGGGUGGGUGGGGAUGCGGAAGAAAUGGGGGUCCUAACUGGUGGGCACACAGCACUGGAGUGAUUUUUAUCUGUUUACAAUCAUGUCACACUGAAUACUUAUGGGAGCCGGAGAUGAGGGUAGGAAAGGUUUGAUCUUGUAAUAUGUCACUGUGUUUCCUUAGUGGCCAGCCAGCCUUCAGAAUAGCUAAAGGCCUUCCUUCCUUCCAGUCAGCCUGAGAGAGAACACCUGUCCCCUAAGCACCUGGUGUCUCCAUUGGAGGCAGACUGCUCUCAGGAGACUACUAGAAGCUUCAGCCCGGAAGACAGGCUGCUCUCUCAUGCUGGUGGCCCAAAUUGAGAAAGUGGUGUCCCUUCCUGAUUUUGCCACCAGCCCUACCGAAUAGUUGUAAACCAGUAUCAGGAAUUGGGAUCGCUAGAGUGUUUCACGUAUUAGAAGAUGAAUCGUCCUCAUCACAGACCUCCCUGUCAGGACUGUGAUCUAGAAGGCAUCACACACAGCUUUCUGGCACGAAUCACAUUUUGUGGAAGUGACUACUCAGGUUUGUAUAUUUUAGUAUCAAUAAAGAAUUGCACAGGUUUGAAUAGGAAAAAUGUAUUCUAUAGAUUUACAGUUUGAAUUUAGGAAUAUUUCAGUAUAUAUAGUUUUUAUUCGUUUUAAGUGAAUCAUAGUAAAAUCAGUCAUGGUGAUUUAAAAUAGCUAUCAAGAACAAGUUCUUGGAAUUAUCUGUUGUAUCUGUGAUAGGAAACCAUUUUACAGUAUUAAAUUACUUUAUUACAGUUGUAGAGUUGAAUUACACUGGAUUCUCCCUCGUUAGCAUUCUGUAUUUGAUUUUAGCUGAAAGGUCACCAAAGUUAGGACCCAUGUUUUAAACUUUUGAAUAUUCCACAAAAGAAAAAACUAAGGAAAAUACUGAAAUUACAGGUCUUUGUAAAGAAUAGCAUAUUUUUAAGCAUGCUUUUGGGAUAGUAGAAGAGUCUCUAUGAAAUAUUAAUCUGCCCUAGUUUCUUAUAAAUUCAGCUGUGGGAGGGGCCAGUAGAGUGUUUCCCUCCAAUUCCAGGAUUCCUAGUGAAGCAUGGAACUGUCGUGUUUACAGUUUGCUAAACAUAUGCUGUCCGUGGAAAAGGAAGCUAAUCGGAAGCAUCCAUGAUACAGAGAAAUGAAAGCCAAGACACCAGUUCCAGGAUGAUGGAAGUUCAUAUCCGUACGCAAAUGCUGAACCUGGUGCUGCUGCCUAGGGCUCAGGCAGAUUUGAGAGUUGAGUAGGGAACACAGGUGCCUCUAAGGUAUAAUGCACAAAAAUACAGAUUUUCUCUCAGAGAGGUUUUAAUUUUAAAUUUGAUGUAUUUGCAAGUGGAUUGAGUUUUGAGCCUGUGUUCUCACUGGAUCCUAAUUCUUGUUAGAAACCUAUCACUGGCAUAACCUGGUUUAGAAGAGUGAAGAGGACAGAAGGAUUGUGGAUGGGUCUGCCCUUUAGCUAGUAUCCGCUAACAUGGGGCAUUACUACUUCAGUUUCUGUGUUUGUGCAGAAGCAGGGAGGAGGUAAAAAGCUAGUUUGGAGCUGGUUAGACCUGGUCUAGGCCCAGAGAAUUUGGCCACUGACAGCCUUUCUCUUUUCCUGGUAAUGCUGGUUUGAAUCAGAGGCCUCUCACUUCUCCUUAACAGGAGCACUGACACUGUGGGCCUCUCCCCAUGACUACCCCAGGGGCCUGGGUGGGAGUGGCUGUAAGCAGCAGUUGGGCCAUUGCCCCCUUUCCUUCUGCCCUCGUGGUCCUUGAGCAGUUGUGUGCACACUCUUCCAGGUAAUCCUGUCUCCUCUCUCUCCCAGUGACCGCCCCAAUCAGCUGUUGCUAGAGCGAUGCUGUGAACGAUACAGGAAAAGUCAGUAAAUCCCUUUAUCCUUAAUCUCCCUUCUUGGUUUUCGACAGAAAAUAUUAAGGAAGAGCAAUAGGAAAUAGAACUACUGUAUUAUAACACUGUGAACAAGAACAUCAGCAGCAGCAGAAUUGUCAGCCUUCCUGCGUCCUGUGUGGGAAUGUGUCCAUGCCUUAUAGGUACUAGUGCUUCGUCCAUUGUCCAGGGAGUGUCCUGAGCUUUCACUGGUCUUUGAAGUGCAGAUCUGCUAUAAGCUGUCUGGAGCUGCAAGGUUGCAGGAAUCCACAGGAGCGUGAGCUGCUGUGAACCCCUAGCCCACCCAUCCCCAAGCAGGAUCUUCUUCUCACCUUUUCUUCCUCCUCUAGCACUUCUCUUUCCAAGUGUCUUAAGCAGAUGCAAUGUCUUAAAGCAGAUGCAAAUGCAUUUGCCAUCUUCUCCAUUAGGAAAAUGAUGGUUAUGUGAUAUGUUAUAUUUAGGAAGUAGUGUGUAAGGUAUCCUGAAAAGGUUUGCUCUCAAGCUAGAAGGACAUUUCACCCUGUGGGUCACUGUCACCUUGUCAGCGUGCCGGCUCUCAGUGGUCCCCAGGAGGAUGGGGAUAGCUGAGAUCGUGGAGAAUGGGAAAUACCAUUGCAUCUCUUUGAUUUAACACUCAUGGCUCACCUUUAGUAGAGUUGUUAAUAAGUUAGAAACUUGUGUCCCUAAGGCCCAAGAGAAAAGAUGAGCUUCUUGGGAGGAUUCUGGGUUUGUUUUCCCCUCAGAAUUAAAAAAUAGUUUUUAAUUCAGCUACUUUUUCCCCUCAGUUAAAAGGUAGCAGGAGCUAUUGGCUGAAAUUUGUUACAGUGAAUGAAUGUGGAGAAUAAAUAAGAACAAACCCUGUAGGAUUCUUGUUGACGUAACUUUCCAUCCCACCUCUCCGCCUCUCCUUCAUCACCAGCCUUCAUCAGGUUGGUUUAGUUUACCUGGCCGUACACACGAGCUGCUCAUCAACAGUUCGUAUCUUCUCACUGAGCCCGGGCCAGAUGCUCUCAGAAGGCCUUCUCAUGCUCCUCUUCGUUAGGCUUAGUGAAAACCUUAAGACCUGCAGUUUGUGCCCCUCAGUUCAGUCAGACCUCAGCUUUAAAUGUCGAUUUACUCUGUCUUGUUCCCUGAAAGUGUUUCUUGUGACUAAGCAUUUGGUGUCAUUAUCCCAUGCCAUUUAUCUGCUGUAUAGUUACUAUAUUAUUUUUGCUGAUUCCUACUGCUGGCAGAUGCCAUCCCAGGCCCACAAAAUCCCAGUGUUGCAGUCACCACAGCUGUCAGAAACAAGUUUGCAAUCCAUACUUCUUGGUUCAAUUUUUUUUUUUAAUGGACAUUCAAAUCUGUAAAUACUACACUGCUCUUAAGACCUGAUUUGAAAUUUCACAGGAAGGCCUAAUCCUAUAGUCACAAGGUAAGGACAGUUGAGUAGUGUAAGAACCCCAACCUGCUUGCAGAGAACCUUGGUUUUCAUAGAAAGGAAAGGCUGAAGGUUUUCUAGCAUUGUUGCCCUUCUUUGUCUGUCAGUCAGUUCACCCUCUGUGAUUCUCCAUGGACCCGCAUUGCAGAAAAUCAGUCCCAUAUAUUAGUGAGCCAUGUACUGCCCAAUCCGGGGGCUCCUGGGGUGUGGUGUGUCCACCAGUGACUCUCCGGACACUAGCUUCAGUAAGGAUACUUCUUAUUUCGGUUGAGAAUGCAGAGGCUUUUAUUCGUGGACUCACAUCACUGCAUAGCACAAAGAAUGUGAUUGCCAUUUGCUGCGUGAGAAAAAGCUGGGCUCCCUAUUUCUUUUUUGGGUUGGACUCUGCCGUGCAGCCAUAGGACACCAAGCCUCACGCACUUUCCCCUUGGGACAGUAGUGUUUGGGUGAAUGUUACUGCAUCCCGUUUUUUUUCUUUUCUUUUUUUUUUUUUUUUUUUUGAGACGAAAUCUUGCUCUUGUCCCCCAGACUGGAGUGCAAUGGCACGAUCUCGGCUCACUGCAACCUCCACCUCCCAGGUUCAAGGGAUUCGUCUGCCUCGGCCUCCCAAGUAGCUGGGACUACAAGCGCGCACCACCACUCCCAGCUAAUUUUUGUAUUUUUAGUAGAGGCGGGGUUUCACCAUGUUGGCCAGGCUGGUCUCAAACUCCUGACCUCAGGUGAUCCACCCGCCUUGGCCUCCCAACAUGCUGGGAUUACAGGCGUGAGCCAACACACCGGACCUUCAUUUUUUAAAUUAAGCUGGGACACAAGUUUUGCCUCCAGGCUGGAUGUUGAUCCUGCUCUGUGCUAGACAGAUGUGCGGAGGGACUGUUCCGGGCUCGGCUUGACCUUUUCCUACCUAGUUUCUCCCUCUUGUCCUGCACAAGAGGACUAACUGAACUCUAACGUCAGAACGGCUGACGAGCAGUUGAUUGUCCUUGCUUGUGUUGUUGACAGGGGUGGGUGGGGUGGGAGCAGGGGUAUGGAUAUUGCAUAAGUUAUUGAAAUGCUGACCCCCGUUCAGGAAACCAUGCAGCCCCUUCCCUUCCCUUCCCUUCCCUUCCUUUCCCUUCCCUAGCCAGGGCUCAGGUACCUCACUCUCCUGCCUUGUGCGUAGCUCCUGGGGCCCCGGUCAGUCCCCAGCAGCCUUGGCACACAGUGUCUGGAGCCUCUGCUCCUGCUGCAAAAGCAGAAACCAUGUGAACCUUCUGGCCAGUACUGGAAAGGGGAAUGCUAUUUAUUUUUAUAUUGUGUAUAUUUUGUCGUGGUCUGCUGAUUCCCUGUUUCACUGAGAGCGACACUUACCUCAAUAGUUAGUUCAAUAUUGUGUGUUGGAUAAUUUUUUAAAAGAACUUUUUAAAAAGCUUUUUGAUCCUUGGAGGUCUGUAGAUUUAUUUCCAUAUGAACUGGUUAUUUUGUAUAAAGUACAUGCUUAAAAUAGCAA